CUCUUUCGCUCCGUGUCCCGCUGCUGCUCCUGUGAGCGCCCGGCGAGUCCGUCCCGUCCACCGUCCGCAGCUGGUAGCCAGCCUGCCCCUCGCCUCGACUCCCUUUCACCAACACCGACACCCACAUUGACACCUCCAGUCCGGCCAGCCGCUCCACUCGUUGCCUUUGCAUCUCCACACAUGGCGUCCUCCGCGCAGAGCGGCGGCUCCUCCGGGGGACCCGCGGUCCCCACCGUGCAGCGGGGCAUCAUCAAGAUGGUCCUCUCAGGGUGCGCCAUCAUUGUCCGAGGUCAGCCUCGUGGUGGGCCUCCUCCUGAGCGGCAGAUCAACCUCAGCAACAUUCGUGCUGGAAAUCUUGCUCGCCGGGCAGCCGCCACACAACCUGAUGCAAAGGAUACCCCUGAUGAGCCCUGGGCAUUUCCAGCUCGAGAGUUCCUUCGAAAGAAGCUGAUUGGGAAGGAAGUCUGUUUCACGAUAGAAAACAAGACUCCCCAGGGGCGAGAGUAUGGCAUGAUCUACCUUGGAAAAGAUACCAAUGGGGAAAACAUUGCAGAAUCACUGGUUGCAGAGGGCUUAGCCACCCGGAGAGAAGGCAUGAGAGCUAAUAAUCCUGAGCAGAACCGGCUUUCAGAAUGUGAAGAACAAGCAAAGGCAGCCAAGAAAGGGAUGUGGAGUGAGGGGAACGGUUCACAUACUAUCCGGGAUCUCAAGUAUACCAUUGAAAACCCAAGGCACUUUGUGGACUCACACCACCAGAAGCCUGUUAAUGCUAUCAUCGAGCAUGUGCGGGACGGCAGUGUGGUCAGGGCCCUGCUCCUCCCAGAUUACUACCUGGUUACAGUCAUGCUGUCAGGCAUCAAGUGCCCAACUUUUCGACGGGAAGCAGAUGGCAGUGAAACUCCAGAGCCUUUUGCUGCAGAAGCCAAAUUUUUCACUGAGUCGCGACUGCUUCAGAGAGAUGUUCAGAUCAUUCUGGAGAGCUGCCACAACCAGAACAUUCUGGGUACCAUCCUUCAUCCAAAUGGCAACAUCACAGAGCUCCUCCUGAAGGAAGGUUUCGCACGCUGUGUGGACUGGUCGAUUGCAGUUUACACCCGGGGCGCAGAAAAGCUGAGGGCGGCAGAGAGGUUUGCCAAAGAGCGCAGGCUGAGAAUAUGGAGAGACUAUGUGGCUCCCACAGCUAAUUUGGACCAAAAGGACAAGCAGUUUGUUGCCAAGGUGAUGCAGGUUCUGAAUGCUGAUGCCAUUGUUGUGAAGCUGAACUCAGGCGAUUACAAGACGAUUCACCUGUCCAGCAUCCGACCACCGAGGCUGGAGGGGGAGAACACCCAGGAUAAGAACAAGAAACUGCGUCCCCUGUAUGACAUUCCUUACAUGUUUGAGGCCCGGGAAUUUCUUCGAAAAAAGCUUAUUGGGAAGAAGGUCAAUGUGACGGUGGACUACAUUAGACCAGCCAGCCCAGCCACAGAGACAGUGCCUGCCUUUUCAGAGCGUACCUGUGCCACUGUCACCAUUGGAGGAAUAAACAUUGCUGAGGCUCUUGUCAGCAAAGGUCUAGCCACAGUGAUCAGAUACCGGCAGGAUGAUGACCAGAGAUCAUCACACUACGAUGAACUGCUUGCUGCAGAGGCCAGAGCUAUUAAGAAUGGCAAAGGAUUGCAUAGCAAGAAGGAAGUGCCUAUCCACCGUGUUGCAGAUAUAUCUGGGGAUACCCAAAAAGCAAAGCAGUUCCUGCCUUUUCUUCAGCGGGCAGGUCGUUCUGAAGCUGUGGUGGAAUACGUCUUCAGUGGUUCUCGUCUCAAACUCUAUUUGCCAAAGGAAACUUGCCUUAUCACCUUCUUGCUUGCAGGCAUUGAAUGCCCCAGAGGAGCCCGAAACCUCCCAGGCUUGGUGCAGGAAGGAGAGCCCUUCAGCGAGGAAGCUACACUUUUCACCAAGGAACUGGUGCUGCAGCGAGAGUGCCUCCCAGACAACAGCCUCAUCAUCCACCUGAAGUACAAGUAAUAAUUUGAGAAUAUGACAGUGGCAUAUAAAAGGGAGUAGGUGAUGUGAUGGAGGCAGACAGAAGAGGUAAGCGGGUGCAUUCUCUUUAAAUUGUAUUAUUUUAGUGAGAAAAGGAUGGGAGCCUAAGUUAGAGAAGUCAUCCAGGGCUUUGGCCUUCUGUAAGGAAACUCCUCCUAGACAGGGUUGCAAAGAUAACUGCACACAGAUUGAGAACGUGUGCUAGAGGAGGAGUACAGGUGUCUGACAGACCUGGAAUUUUCCAUCGCUUUCCCUGAUAUGUAGUUGUAGAAAAGCUGCUGUCUAUUCGUGCCAAAUCCAAGCUUCAGAUAAGCCCGGAGGAAACCAAGGAGUGCUAAACUCUUACAGGUUGGGGGCUUUUUCUUUCCUUUUUUUUUUUUUUUGGAGGGGGGUUGCAUUGUUUUGAUUUUUGAAUUGAGAGAGUUGUGGGGAGGUCAAAAUGCCCAUCCACGAUUGCCCUCGAACUCCCUAGGUGGGACUCCAGCUCAAGCACUCUGUUCUGGUCAAGUUGAGGCAGGGCACAGGGUGGGCCCAUGAGUGCCAUCCCUUUCCUCUGGUAUCCCAUGCCCCUGGACCCACUCCCUCUACUCUCCCAUGAGGCUGAUGCAGGACUCAUGCCAUGCUGUCAGGGUCUGGGGGUUUCUCCCACCCUGUAGCAGAGGCAGGUUACCCUUCUUGUUAGCAGUGAUGUCUGUUCGUCUUUUAAGGGGUUGUCCAAGUGGGGGAGGAACAAAUCAUAUUUUCCAGCAAUUUAAUUUUAUUAACUCUGAUUUUUUUCCCCUUUUCCAAAGCACAGCUAAAUGGAGCUAAACAUAGACAUGAGGGCUAUAUUUAGUCCUGAUGGUGUGGUAGAGUAGAGAAGGCACAAACACAGAGGUUUAUCUGCUACCUAGUAAAUAUGGGGAGGUGUCAGGACUGUAGAAUUCAAUAGUAAUAAUAAGCAUUUUUAUGGUGCAAUGACAGCUUUGAUACAGGGCAUAAUUUUCUCAGGAUUGCUAUUAAUUGUGCUUCUGCCUAUGAGCGGCCCCCUGGUGAGGGGCUUGGAACACCACACAAGUUAAGCUAUAUUAAACAUCAAUUAAAACAGCAUAAAAUAGAAACUGAAUAAAAUAUGCAAAGGUCAGAGUGGCUGUGAACAUGCAGACAAGGUACUGGGGAAAGAAGGGUUAGGGCCUGGUGAGCCUGGUGCACUGGCGGAUUCAUACUCCCAGCUGCUGUUAGCUUCUUUGGAGCCCAGGUUUAGUAGGUUUGUUGGAGAGUGAAUUAUGGGACCCUCUAGCUUUUCCAAGUUCAAUUAUCCUCAAAGGGGUUUCGGAAACUACUCAUUGCAGGCAGCAAGAGAUGGAAAAAGACAACCAGAUUCUACCAGUGCUGUCCAACAGAACUUUCUAUGUUGGUGGAAAUGUCCUUUGUCUCUGCUGUCCAGUACAGUAGCCACGUAAUGGAUAUUGAGCACUUGAAAUAUGGUUUAUACAACUGAUUAAUAGAAUCUUUAUAAAAUUUAAAUAAUUUCAAGGUAAAUAGCCACAUGGGGCUAGUGGCCACCUUAUUAGACAGCAUAGGACUCUAGACAAGUCCCCUGCACAUUGUGCAUUCUGGCAAUGUUAGGUUUGCAUUGUGUUCUUCUGAAAAAGUCUGCACCUUCCCCCAUGCCAGUGAGUGUGUUUUCUCAAUAACUUUUUUUUUUUUUUUGACCCUUAUCUCUCAUGCUCUUGACACAAACUUCCACAUUUUUUCAUAAGGGUCACACACGAUGCCAAGAAAUGAGAAAGGAGUCAAUGCCGGAUCAAGUCAGACAACCUUGUCCUUAUCCUUGCCUCCUUUUCUCCUGAGAGCCCCUAGUCAAUCUAAUACCAAGUGUUUCCCACUCCCAGAGAGAAAAGAAGGGAAUGGCUUUGGAUCUCUGGCUAAAGAUCACAGACUGCGGAGUCGUCACUGUUCCCACUGAACAUCUGAUUAAGUUGCUGAGUCUGACCCUUGAGUUUCCCAGAACUUGCCAAGAUUCAGAAUUCCCAGAUCAUCCAGGCAGCACGCUCCUGACAGUCUUUGGUCCUUUUGGCACCUGAACUGAAAAUCCCUUUUCCCAUAGCUCUUUCAACACUUGUUGAAUGCUUAUAAUGAAUCCAUUCAUUAGGAUGACACAGUAUAGUGGAACAAAGCACUACACCUGUAAUCAGAAAUCCCAUGUUUAAGUCCUGACUCUUCCAUUUACUAUCUCUGUGACCUUGACAAAAUCAUUUCACCUCCCUGAGGCUUCAUCUUCCCCAAUAAAAAUGAGUGUUUUGGACUAAAUGACCUGUGGGUACUAAGAGGAUGAAGAAAAGAGAGCCAGAGAAAGAGGCCCUUAUUGCAAAGCCUGUCUUCCACAUAGCCUCCCCCUUCUGAUGUCAGCCUGCAUUUAAAGCAGCCCUUUCCUGAGGCCACGGAGAGGCUUCCAGUGAGUCUAGUUACCACUCACCCCACCCACAGGUUGUUCAGCACCAGAGACACCAUGAGCCAGACUGCAUGGCAUUACUGCCUCUGGUGGUUAUUGUACUCAUGUGAACCUCAGGGAAGUCAAGACUGGUCCCCUAUUACUUUGGCAUCCUCAGAGAUGCCGUAAGAAGGCAAGAGGUUCCUUGGCUUAGGCAGUGGGUCCAUAAAGCAAGAGGGGUUUUGUAGUUACCUGAAGUAUGCAGAUCUCCAUGCUGGCUCAAGGGCUGUUUGCCAGCCUUCCUUUACCCAGUAGUCACUAGUCACUGCUCCAAGGAUUGGCCCCAGCCCCCCAGAGCCCCUGUGGAGCCGCCAACACUGCACAGCUCACAAAGGGCCCUGUAGCAUCUCUAACUGAGGAGCUGGUGAGCGGACGCCCUCAGCAGAGGUAUUUUUAGCUACAAUGAUACAGCCUCAUCUUUUUGCAGGACGUUUUGUUUAGUUAUUUUUUUAAUGAAAUAAAUAAGUAAAAUUGAAGACUGUGGUACUUACACCCCAGUGCCAACACCCAAGAAGUUUUGGCGCACACUGUCCCCCCCACCCCCAAACACACACACCACAGGCCUAUAUAAUUAAUCCUCUCUAAAACCAGGUGCUGAGGCUCAGAGUUUGCCAGAAUAUUAGGCCACAGAGACAGUGUGUACAGAAGCAAGAAGAGCUAGAAAUAGAGUGGAGGAAUGAUGCAGACUGGCCCAGUGCAGAGGUGCUUGAGGGCCCUGUGAGCUGCCCAGGCAGCUGGUAACUACCCUGGUUCCUGGUGUUCAGACCUUUGAUGGAUUUGGUGGCUCAAGUGAGUGGGCCUCAACUCCUGGGGAGAGAGUGCCCUUGUAGUAUACAAAGGAUUCAGUUCUAUGCCUUGCUGACAUUUUAAUGCUUUUGUUUUCCUUCUCUUCAUCCUGUCUGGCAUGUCACGUUUUCCUUGGCUCUUUUAUUGUGUAACAUGUGAUCAGGGGCUAAAGGACAUUCGCAGAGCUUGCUUCAGAUCCCAGAGCAGGAUCAGGGUAGUGGUUCUUACCCCAGCUGCACAUUGGAAUCAUGGAGUAUGGAGGCUUAGGAAAGCUACUAAUGCCUGGGCCUCCCUCCAAAGAUUCUGGCUUCAUCAAGCACCAGCUUUUUAACUUCCCCAGAUUUAUUAGUUGAUACCAAGGAAUAACUUUGAUAAUUUUGGUAGGCAUAAUAAUGGCAUUGUGGUUAUGUAAGAAAAUGAACAUAUUUUUUAGAGAUACAUAUUAAAUGAAGUGUUUAAGGUUGAAAAUGGCAUCAUGUCUGGGAUAUACUUUAAAAUGCUUCCACAAAGAAAAGGGGGAUAGAGAUGAAGCAAAUAUGACAACUUUGGUAGUUGUUGGAUCUGGAUGGUGGUUAUAUGGAAGUUCAUUAGUAUCCUAUUUUCAGUAUUUUGAAUUUUUCACAUCAGAAAAGGGUUUUAAAUAUAUACAUACAUUUUAUAUAAAUAUAUAUUAAUGUUGAAGCUCCCCAGGCAAUUUUAAUGUAGAACUAAGAUUGAGAACCACUAGUUAGUUUAGGGGAUUAAAUUUGGAUCACCAUGCCCUAAAAGAUGUGUUUUGUCUUUGGACUUUGUCUAACCUAAGCCUGAUUUUUCUGGAUAAGUUUUCAUGAGUAAUCUGGACUCUUGGUAGGUGGGGGACAGGAUGGCACAAAGAUCAAAUUAGACCUGUAUCUGGAAUCUGACUUCAGGAGCGUACAACUAGACAAUAUUGUCUCUUCCACUGGAUGAACUCACUGUAACCGCCCUGAGAGCUAUUAUACCUUGGAGUUUACCUGCCUCAUCACUUGCCAGCACUGCAUGUCCCAUCCUAUGGACCUCUCUGGCUACACCAGGGCAAUGGAAGACAGCUGCAGCUGCAUUGUAACACAUGCCACAAGAAAGCCCCAGUCCCUUAAGAGUGCUCAGCAGUUUGCCAAGCGGUAUUUGCCUAAAGCUGGGGCAAGAGGACUGAAACUUGUACCUCCCCCCAUUCCCAGGAGUCCACAUGCCCUCAGCUCUGCAUCCGUAUGUGUAUGAGGCCUCUUUUGUGUCUUCAGUGCCUAUUCCAACUCCCAAGCACUAUUUUGCUCUGGCUGGUCAGCAAGUGGGACGAGCAGCAGCUUGCUGCAGCCAACCUAAAUGGAGCUCUGGAGCUCAGGCUGGAAGCUUCCAUGCUACAUUUACAUACCACAUCCUUGCUCAGGACCCUAGCUGAGCACCUUUUCAUUCAGGGGUAGGCUGCUAGUUCUUCUUUCUUGGGGGGUUUUGUGAUUUACACCUAAACAUUAAGCUAUGAAUAGUUUAUGUUUUGCUAAGCAAUACCGAAGCAGAGGAAGCGUUAUGGACUGCCCAGGUCACUCAGCCAGCCCAAAGGUUCGCAUGACACCCUCCCUUCCCAUUGCCCCUGGACCCCUGAGACAGCCCUUUCCGCCAGUGCCUGCCAGUGCACAAGUCACCCCCUGCACCUCUGUAGAAGGGCCUGGCUCAUCUUUGUUUUCCUCACACAGUCAGAGUCAGCGUUGGUCCCACACUGUCCAGUGCUACAUCCAGACUCCAAAUGAGGGGGUUGCUUCCUCAGCCCAGUCCUAAGAACAAGCCUACUGUGUGGCCUCAUCUGUGUUUCUUCAUGGGACUCUGGACAGGAGGAGGCAGGGGCUUCUCCUGACUCUGGAUCACUCUCCAGAGUGCUCCCCCUUUAUAUACCUCCACCUUCCCACUCUUAGACCACAUUGUCAUUGUGUCCGCCCAAGUGCUGAGUGCCUUGAGGGCAAGGACCAAGUCUUUCAUCUCCAUCGUUCCCCAGCACCUGGCAGGGUGCGGAUCACUAUACUGGUUCUAAAUAAGCAAACUAAUGAAUAUGUGAAUCACCGAAGGGCUAUGGCAGGGAAUGCCUUUACACUAAGGGUCGGAAUCCUCAGAUUUAAAAAUUAGUUUCUCAGUCAUUUGGAAUUAUGAACCUAAACUGUGAGAUGAUCUAGAGCAGCAGUCCCCAACCUUUUUGGCACUAGGGAUCAGUUUCAUGGAAGACAAUUUUUCCAUGGACUGGUCGGGUGAGGCAAUGGUUUGGGGAUGAAACUGUUACACCUCAGAUCAUCAGGCAUUAGAUUCGCAUAAGGAGCACACAACCUAGAUCCCUCGCAUGUGCAGUUCACUAUAGGGUUCAAGCUCCUAUGAGACUGUAAUGCCACUGCUGCUGAUCUCACAUGAGGCGGAGCCCUGGCAGUAAUGCUCCCCGCCUACCACUCACCUCCUUAGGCAGGGCUCUAGAUCAGGGGAGACCUCGGCCUAAGUUUGCUUGUAGAGCAGCCUGUGACUGAUGAGGGACAGCCUGUAGCUGGUAAUGGCUAGAGAGAAAUAACCUAUUUGAUAUUCUUACUACUUGCCUUUGGAAUAAAGGGUAAUCUCUCUGUGCCUUGGUUUCUCCCACUUGAUAUUCACAGGUCUCUGAGCAGUCUAUCCUCUCUCCUUCCUUGCCUGGGGCUCUGAGGAGAGUGACCUGCUUGUAGGAGGGUUUCCCUAUGUUUUUCCAGGGCAGUCAGUCAAUUAACACCUGGCCACUUCUUUUGGAAGUUACUCCUCCUGAACCUGAAUGAAACUUCAGGAACAGUCACUCAGCUUAAGCACAACCAUGUACAACAAGCGCUUCUGGAGUCAGUGGCAGUACUGUCCUGUCUAUCAGAAACCUGUCUGAUCAGUAAGUCUUCUUGCCUCCCUUUUGAGUCUAGAGGCUGUCAUCCUGGGUAUACCUUUGAAUCUCCUGGAUGUUUUUUAAAGCAUUGAAGGAAGUCCUGUCACCACCCCUAGAGAUUGCAAGGUAUUUGAUAUAGCAUCUAGAUUUGAUCUACACUGGUAUUUUUAACAGCAACAGUGCUGAUAAUACGAGCCUGGCGCUGAGAAGCACUGUCUCCAAGAGUCCUCACUAGAAGGAGCUGGAGUGGCACUUGUCCCCCGAACAGUCCACUGCUGGCCUCCCUUUCCCAAAGGCGGGUGGGAAGGCAGAGCACUUGUGUCGUCCUCCUUAGCUAGUUCUGAGACAGGACUCCCAUAUUGCGCAGUUGGUGGUGCAGCUUCCCACCCACCCACAGGCCCACAUACACAUGCACACAAAGCCCACUGCUUCUUAACUUUGGGCAGAUCUGUGGAGGGGAGAUAGAUCUAUCUGUGGAUCAAGAUUCAGUUUUGCUUUGGCGGGCAGUUGUGAGAGAGAACAGUCCACAGCUGUGUCUGCAAUUUGUUACCAGAGAUGAAGAUUUUUUUUAAAUUCUAGCUCAAAGAAUGCUUCCCUGUAUCCAUCCCACCAGCUCCCAAGCAUCACAUCCCACCCAUUGGUAGCAGAAGAGCCUGCCUUAGCAGUGAGAGGCAAGGCCAGACACCAGUUGAAAUCCCAGACAGCUUCCUACCCUCCCUCUAUAUCUUGUCAGAUAUUUCAAGCUUUAAGUCCUUAUUCGUGCUCUGCCUACUUGGCUGGCUGUUCUUGCACUUGAGCGGCUUGUUUGCCUGGACAGGUCCAAGCUGUCUGAGCCAUCAGCAGCUGCACCUCCUCCCUCGCGCCUUCUGUCUGAGCCAACCUUGAUUCACAGUAGUGCAGAUGGCCCCAGCCAUACCCAGGGAUGUCUGCCACUCCCAUCCCCUCUCCUGCCCUGCUUUCCCAAGAUGAAGGGGCUGGGUCAGGCCUUGCCCGCAGGUCAACGUGGGGCUAAAAUGAAGACCGCUCUUAGUUCAUGUUCUGGCAUAUUAAUCAGGGUGACAUGAUAAAAAGAAUUUAUCUGAAACUCAUAGAACAGGGCAAGGUUUAAGUUCAUAUUUUGCAGAAAACACUUUCCAGCCUUCAUCAGCGCUAAUCUGUUUUUGAAAAUGGCCUUAAUCCCACCCACUUUGCUCCCUAAGUAUUUAUAGGAGCUGAGAGUCAAAAAAGCACAUGUCAGAAAUCACCUUUCUUCCUUUUCCUACCCUUACCUCAUUUUAAUAUAGACUUUGGCAACUUCUCAAAGUACAAUGCUCAGUUUUUCAGUCUGGUUCAAGGUGCUUAAAGGUAGUGCCCUGUAAUACACCAUUAUAAUCAAUUAGUUUCCCUUCUCCUUGUCCCUUUCCAACAGAAAUGAAAUGAUUGGUAACAAGUAUGAGAGGGGUCAUGGGUGACCUUGUUCAAGAGAAAGAUAUGGCUGCAGCAGCCCCAGGACACCACUCUGCCUUUCCCCAUUGCUGGCUUCUUGGUGAGCAGCAGAAAUUUGGAGCUGUACAGGAAUCAGAUGUCCCACCUAGCAGGCUCUGCCGGAGCCAGACAUAGCCAUCCACUCUGGCAGCAGCCUAUCGAAGGGAGAGAAUCCUGGGGCAGCAGCCUACCAUGCUGCCCCUUCCACUUUAGAUAGGGCCAUGCAAUGUAAAUACAUUAUUUGUAUUUACAUUUGGGUCAUCUGCAAACCAAAGCGAUCUCAGCAGCUGCUGGAAUGCCAUUGGUACAGCCAUACCAACAUUUAUAUUAUUCACCCUGAUGUCUAGAUUGCUAUUACUGACAUUAUUUUAAGGCUUUUUCUCCCUUAAGAGAAAGCUCUUCCAGCCCUAGGCUGCUUAAAUAGGGAGGAACAACUUCCUUUUUUUUUUUUUUUUUUUAAGAGACAGAGUCUUGCUACGUUGCCCAGGCUGGUCUCAAACUCUUGGAUUCAAGAGUUCCUCCCUCCUCAGCCUCCCUAGUAGCUAGGACUAUAGAUGUGCACCACCCUGCCCAACAAACCUUUUUUUUCAAUUGAGGAAUAUUAGGAUUGAGAUAUAUUAUGGACUUUCUAUACAACUUGGGGUGUUUUCUUCAGGAUAAGUAUAUUUUUAAUCUUUAAUAAUGAUAAAAUACUUUACUGGCACCUAAGGAACAAUAAAAUACUGACUAAGAGGCCUGAAGAGGCAUCUGCUCCUAUCUCUAGAAUUUGAAACCAGUCGUUUGGUGAGCUCUCAUGCUGGAGUGGGCAUGGGGCCGUGUGGGUGGCAGAAAAUCAAGGGGUCUCAUUCCACUGAAAUGUCAUGGUUACCUCAGCCUAUGGCUGGUGUUUGCCCUCUUCUCUCCAAUUCGGUAAGGAAGAAAGCUCCUUUACCAAAGCGUAGAGUACCUGGGCAGAACACCCAGGAACCUUUUUCUUUCUCUAAAGUCACAUGAUAGAUCUCACCACAGCAGUCAAUUUCUUGUUCUUCCUAACUGCCCCUACCCUCCUUGUGUAGAUUACAUGUCUUUUUCUCUUCCUGUUACAAUUGUUACUUAACCUCUUAACCAUAGGAAACUUGCUUUCUUGGAUCCAUUAUUUUCUUGUGUCUGACCAAAUCUUAGUGAUCUGCCUGCUUUUGUUUUUGAUCCAGAAAUUCUAGUCAUUUGGAAGUACUGGACAGAGGGUCAGCUAUAGGCAUAGGCCAGGUUCUUGAGGUAUAGGUCCCAAGGACCUGAACUGACAAUAUUUGUCUUAGUCCUUAAAGUAACCAUCAGAUUCACUGCCAGAAACUUUAGCCAGCAACAAAAUGUGGCAGAUACACUACCACCCCCACACCCCCUGUUAUGUCAGAGAACAUCCCUGAAGCUGCUCAGCACAGUGUAGAGGGGACAGCAGAGCUCCAAGAGGGAUCCUGCUUUCCUCAUCCUGCAGUGAGGUGUGAUUCAGAAGAGCACACAGCACGCCAGAGCCUUGGAGGUUAGGGUAGGGAGGUUCUUCCCCCUGUUCUCAUGUGGCUUACCUGCAAACCUGCCUAGAUGGGGACUUACAGAGGGCUAUCAUCACCCCAGAGUGCUUGGACUGCUCAGAUCAACUAGGUAGCUGCUUGCUACCAGGAUGUCCAGGACAUGAGGGGGCUACGUAAGUACAACUAUUAAUCACCCAGGAAGAUGUUUUCCUGUUGUCCCAGUACAGGGCCACCUCUCAGGCUCCAUGUGUCGCAUUCACUGAAGUUUUAGACAUGAGAGGUGGCUCUGUUCUCUCUGGGGGACAAGUCAGGAAAAGAUUGCCUAGCUGACUCUUCCCUGGUCUCAGUUCCGAAUGAAAAGCCUGCCAUGCGGCCUUCAGCAUCUGCUACUCCCCGUGCCACACCUGAUCCCAUCUCAAGUCAUUUCACACCAGCAGAGGGAAGCCCUGUUCCAACUCCAGCAGCAGCACCACUCGGGGAGGGGGGGCAAACUCUUUACCCUUGUGGUAUUUUGUAAACUGCAGCAGCGAAGCCUGAACUUCCAGGAGGGAAAUGAAAUGACCUUGGCAGGUAACAGGUUCAGGACAGCCAGCAUUUGUCUUGGUUGUUGGUUUCCACAUGUUAAAUGCUUCUAGUUGCUCCUGACCUUCCUUGCCUGCCUUUGUUGGUCAAGUCCUAUAGGCACUGUGGCAUUUGUGCAGGGAGCAGGGGAGAGGAAGCUUUUCUGCUUUACUCUGGCACCUGACAAGGGCUCUCUAUCCAGCAUUGGCAUUGCCAGUGGGGAACUGCUGAAGUAGCACUCUAGAGUAUCACCCGGGAGACCCCUCUGUCUCCUGCCAAGCUAAACAAACCCUGCCCAUGCACUCUUCUGAAUCACACCUCACUGCAGCUUUGUUCCUUCUUCCCCAGUACUGCUCAGGGCACCGCCUUAUGGGAAAGUCCUGUGUGUCAGCAAAAGAAGCACUUGAGGAGAAACAAAUUGAUAUAGGAAGGGGGAGUGCCACCCAGUCAUCUUUUAAGUACAAAGAAAGGUCAUCGGAGCUGUAUGGGGUCCAGGUUGGAUUAUUGUUGACUCUGCCUUGCUGUGGCAAAAGGGCCAGCUCUCUGGGUCCAACCUUGGGCAUUGCCAACCCCAUCCAGCUGCUGACAGCCCAGCACAAAGAAAACACAUGCUGUGUACACACAGAUGGGUUUGCAUGUCAGCAUGAGCCCAUUUUUAGCCUUUGGCCAGGAAGGGCAGUUCACAACACAGUAAUUUAAUUAAAUUUGCCUCCCUCCGUGGCCCACAUAUUUGAAGAGGUUUGGGGGGAAAUGAAUCUGGCUGAGGAACAUUACCCUGCCGCUCUGGCACUGCCCCAGAGCCAAGCCACUGUACCAUAAAGGGUCUCACCAUCCUGAAUACGACCCAGGACAUCUGUCUGCACUGCAGGCUCUCUGGCCGGGCUGCCUGCUGGCACAUCUGGCAAGGCAGCCUCUGGAAGCAGUCCGUCUCUAUCACAGGCAAGCCACCAGGGGCAAAAUAAGGGACUCCCUACCCCCUACUCAAGACCUGCUGGCAACAACUUUAGCAGUAACUCACAAUAUUAGCUUUCAUCACAGAUUUCAGUGUAUUUAGAGUGGAGAGGACAGAAUAAGAGAACCCUCUACCCUCAACUAACAUUGAAGCCUCAAUAACAGCUAUGAUCCUAACUUCAUUGCUGUUAAGGCCACAUACCUGUACUUCUGUCCUGGAAAUGACCAGUAUUUAGGGACCUGAAAUUGAAUCCCUUACCCUUACUUCCCAUGAACUUAUUACCACAUUUCACAUCUCAAAUGUCCAUCAGUUUUGUCCAUUAUGUCUGAGCUUAACCCACACUCCAAACUCCAAAGACCUGCCCCCCUCCCCACCUCAGCCAGCUAGUUCCUCCUUGAACUGAGUUCAUCAACUCAUCAGGAGGCCACUUCUCCUGUGGUCACCCCCUGGUCCAGAGAAUCUGCCCAUGAUGGGUAGUCCUUUCUUAUUGCUAACCCGUAACCUCUCAGUCCGCCUUUUCUGUCCUAAGUCAGCUGUACCAAGCCUGCUAGGGAAGAGCAUUCUCUUUGGUUAUCUUUCUCUCUCCCCAUCAAUAGCACAUCCUCCUGGCUAACUAAUGUCUCUUGUGUAAUGAUAGCAGCACCUCUGAGAGAAAGGGAAUUUCUCUGGCACAGUUCGUCUCAACACCAGCAUAACACAGGCUGUUGCUUAGGAGUGGGAAUCAUUAGAGUCAGGCCAUUAUUGGAGGGGACCGGUCUCUAGGGGAGCUAGCAGAAAUUGCCGCUCCUUAAUGGAUGGAAACUCAUUUGCCUGAAGCCCCUGCCCUCCUCUUUAUUUUCUCUGCAUUCCUCACCUCCCAUUGCUUCCCAGCUUUGAAGUUGAAAAGAGAGGUAACUCCACCCAAUGCACAUUUCUGCUAAAUUAACUUGGUUAGAAGAAAUCCUUGCCUGAAAGCACUGUUCUUUUAGAAUGUUUCUAUUGGGACUUCACUUGAAACCAUCAUGAAGAAGACAAAUUCUAAUUAAAUGUAUGUGAUAAAAUUAUAGCCAGGGCCACUCUGUUCCCAAGAGAGGAUUUGAGAUGGGAGGAAGAGGGGACAAUUUCCUAGCUUUCUGGACCCCAGUUUCAGGGUAGACCCCUGAGUCAACCUGGGCUGCCAGAGCUUUCCCUCUGAGGGUCCCCUUGCUUACACAACACUAGGAAGGCCAGGGAGGUAGAGCGGGACUCCAGGCUUCUCUGCUUCUCCAAGGGUCUGCAUGACCUUGAACAGACCUCUAACAUGAUUUAGCUUUCUGCAAGCCCUCCUGUCAUGUUGGGAUAGAUGUUACCUUACUACCCUGCACUCUUGUAGAGAGAAGGGGAAGGCCAUGGAAGCAACACAUGCCCCUUUUGGUUUAUUAGCCAUGGGGCUGCCAUCAGAGCACACAUGCCCUGAAGAGAAAGGAAAGUUGCCUGAUUUCUCAGCUCUUCCUGUUUGAAUGAAAUCAUGAGUGGGCACCAUCUGUCUCAGAGCAUUAAGCACAGAUAACAGUACUGGUGGGAAAGGCCUUCCCCCCUCCCAAAAGGGAACUAUAAAGGAUUGCAUCAAACUGCAAACUCCAGGGGGCACUAAUCACUUUGCCAUUUCUGUAAAUGGCGCCCCCUGGAGUUGUAAGUCAUGGUGGCCCUGCCGGCGCUCAGCAAUUGCGCUAGGUCGCGAACCCAGAGACUACAGGUAAGGUCUCUGCAUCACCAGCUAUGUGACACCUGGGCAAGGCACAUCUUCCUGGGCUUCAUUUUCCUCAUAAAUAAAAUGUGAGGGUUCAACUAGAUUUUCUGAAUUAACUUGGAAGUUCUCAUUGCCCUCUCCAUAUCCCGGAAGUUAGGAACCAUGAACCUGUGUUCUGUCUCAGUGUCAAUUGUCAUCCCCAGGUCGGCCAGCCUCGAUAACAUACCCAGAAUGAGAAGGCACCCUCGGCUGACAUAACACCACUAGUCGGAGUGGAUGUGGACUUACACAUGAAGGGGGAAGGAUUAAGGAAAGGGAAAGCCUCCAGCGGGCACAAUGGAUGAAACAGCAAGCGCACAGAAUGGGCCAAUGCCUUAUUCUUCUUGUAUUCAUCCUUCUCUGUGGCUUCAGAGCCUUUUUUCUGACACACAUGCACACAGCACCUCCAGUGCUUGCCGUCUCUCCCCCUCAUGAGAGAAACAAAAUGAAAUGCAAACAUGCUUUGAAAGAGCACAGUCUUGUCCUGUCCCUCUGCAUCCCCUCUCCUCAUUUCUAAUGAAAAAAAUAGUCUUCCCUUUCCCUGGUUCCUUCAACAGUCUCUUCCUUAGGUUAUUUUUUUCCUCUCUCCUUUCCUACUCCAUCCAGACUUCCCCCUGCCUAAUCUUAAAGAGAUGAAUUGGAAGAAUAUGCAGUCGUGUCAGAAGGAUGCCAUUGUCAGUUCACACAGGCAGACACUAAUAGGAUAAAGUAUUAUCUGACUUCCUUUAAGUCCAGAAAUUAAGUCUUCUUGCAAUGGCAAUAGAUUAUAACUUAUAACCACUGUGGCUGGCAGGCUGCAGAAACAGGCUGUUAGUAUCUGAGGCCUCAGCUCCAUUUCUGGGCCUAUUGUGAGGGAUGCACUCAGCAUUCCUCCAAACACAGCUGCAUGAUCCAGGGAACUGGCACUUGGCUCCUGGAUGGAACUGCCUCUGUGGAGAGCUGCCUAUAACUCAUUCAGUUCACCUGCCGUGGGAGAAGCUGUCUGAAUGGUCUUAAUGAACCUGGAUGAGUGGGCAGGUAAAGGGAGGAAGCCAGGGUCUUGAAGACUGGGAAGAAGUAGCCCGAGGCAAGGAAACCAAACUUUGCACAGGGAACACUUAGUGUGUGAAAGCUCUUCUCAGUCAUCCUUGCUGACUCAUUGAGCAGGUAGUAACUUAUCUAGUGACUAAAUCAGCACCAGCUUAGAGACACAGGGAAAUGAGGGUUGAGACCUUAAAGGAACUGUAAAAGAGACUACAAAUUAAGGAGUUGCCCUGGAGAGGAAAUAUCAUGAGAAAUGUUAGGAAGAAAGAGCCAUCAUUCUUCAAAAUGGAGGGCCUCAUGCAGGAUUUCCUAGGUCCUGUUAUGGCAGAUGAGUGUACUCAAAUGGGGAAUAUGGGACAGGAAACCUGAUACAAUAAUUAAUUGAAGGGUAUUUUUUUAUUAGUGGGGCUAUAAGAAGGUAGGUGGGGGCUGGGUACAGUGGCUGACGCCUGUAAUCCCAGCACUUUGUGAGCCCAAGGUGGGCGGAUUGCCUGAGGUCGGGAGUUUCAGACCAGCCUGGCCAGCAUGGUGAAACCCCGUCUCUACUAAAAAUACAAAAAUUAGCCAGGCGUGGUGGUGCGCACCUGUAAUCCCAGCAACUCGGGAAGCUGACGCCAGGAGAAUCGCUUGAACCCGGGAGGCGGAGGUUGCAGUGAGCCGAGAUCACACCACUGCACUCCAGCCUGGGCAACAGAGCAAGACUCUCUCUCAAAAAAAAAAAAAAAAAAAAAAAGAAGGUAGGAGGGUAUGAAAGAAACAAGUAGAUCAAGUACUGUUUCUUUGGCAUCCUAUAAUUGAUUUAAACUGUAGUAAUUACUCUAGUAAUGUUCCUGAGUGUACAGAAUGAACAAACCUGAAAGCCUAAGUACUAUCUUGGUCCGUCUAGCUCCCACACCUAGCUUGAGAGUAGCCUCUCAUAUCAAUGCUUCCCUGCUAUCCUUUCAAAACUCUUUUUGAUGGGAUAAGUGGGCAAAGAUCAUGCCAUCGUCUCAAAUGCUAACUUCCUUUGACAAGACAGUUUCUCCCAGGGAUAUCCCCCACAGGCCUAGGCCAAAUCUCUGACUCACUGCAAAGGUCCAUGUACACUGAACUGAUAGACAUCACUAUUUUUAUUGGAAAACACAAUUUAUAUAACACUCUUCCUCUGGAAUAAUACUCUUUUUGUGGACAAAUACCGAGUUGCUCCCUCUCUUCUCCCCAGCACACCCCACCCCCCUCCCCAUGACUGUGUUAAUAGAAAUGAGGAAAUGGGUUUAGAGCAGAUCCCUGAGUGAGCCUGUCAGGGUCAGGAUUAAAUUACAUCCCUGAAGGCUGGGUUGCUUCCCCAAGCAGUGGACAGCCUCCAGGAUAGGGAACAGGACUGUUGUGGGUAGGUGGUUUGGCCCAAGUACUGACAGCAAAGCUGGCGUGUACCAGAGGAUAAAACCUGUGAUCAUCCUAAAAUCUAAUUCUAGCCUCUCAUUAGGAAAUCAAAAUGCAUUCUUUCUUCGCCUCUCUUGGAAAGUUGAUCUCCCUGCUUUUCUUCUCCUCUGUUUCAUGCCAUGAAUUUCGCACUAACAGUCCUCCCCCAUCCAGGGUCCAGCCAGCCUCUUGCUUGCUAAGGCAGAGGAAUCUCCCUGGCUUUCCUCCUUGACUGCAUUGCAGCCCCUUAGCCUGUGUAUCUGCCAUAGAGCUCCAUUCUUCUCUCAUUUGCUCCAAUUAUGGUGCUUUUUGUCUGCCUUUCUUUUCUCCUAGCUCUGCAAUACUGCUCGGAAGCCCCACCGGCCCUUUCAGUGCUACCUUCUUCCUCCUAGUGCCUCCCCACUCCCCACUCCCAGUCCUGGUAACACUUAAUGGUCAGGGAGGAUUUCAUCACUGACCUGAGUAAUAAGGCUAUGACUGCUCUGUGCCAGAGAAACAUGGGUAGGGGAGAAGACAUUAGGAAGUUUACCUUCUUGGUAAAGGACCUAGGCUUCCCAAGGUCCCAGCCCUCAGCUUAUGCAUGACUAUCAGCACCUUUACUUUCUUCUGGCUCACCACAAGGAAAGGUAAUCUAUUCCUGGACUAAAUCAGUGCCUUGGGACAGCUAUAGUGCUGGUGUAGGGAUCAGAGCACAAGGCAAGGUUUUCCUGGGAGGAUAAGUAUAACCAUGUUUUUCACAGUGAUCGGGCUUAUAGAUACUAUUGUCUCUGACUUCUAGAUCAUCAUCCUUCUUCUCUGGAGUAGCACAAUAGGCAUGUCUCUCUUUGGACAUAUACAAUGUUCAAGAAUAGGGGUGGUGAUGGGGGCUUCUCUGUUGAUCUGUGUGUUUGUGUGUAUUGUCAAAUAACUGUUAUCUAGCAUUUGCUAUAUGGUGUGGAGCACUAAGUGUGAGAUCUAUGUCACACACAUACAUAUAUAAUUAUAUAUGUAAAAUUUCAAUUCUCACAAUCUGUGAAGUACUGAGGUAGAUAGUAAUAUUGUCUGUAUUUUUUAGGUGAAGAAACUGAGUCUUUUUCCAAAGUCACACAGCUAGUAAGUGAUGGGAACUAGGAUUCAACACAGGAAGACUGGCUACAGAGUCUGUGCUUGUAAGCACUAUGCUAUAUUGCUGUGUGUGUGUGUGUGUGUAUUUCACUGAUCUAGUUGCUGAAGCCCUUAUCACUGCUCCAAGAAGUAAUUUACUUCAUUUUAAUUUAAAGCAAAGAUGAAAACAACUUAUCCUACUGUCCAAAACAUUCUUCCCCUUGCAUAGGAGAGGGGUGCUUCCUGAAAGGAGUGAGACCAAGAGAGUUGCUCUGAGCCAAAAGCUGCCUUGCAGUUUAGCUGAGGCAGGAUUUAGAAAUGGCGUGAACAGUGCCUGCAUUAGCCGAUGGCAUGGAGUGCUGAGUGCCAGCAGAGGAGAUAAAAUCAGACAUAUGUUUGGAUAUAAAUGUUCCUCUCUCUCUUCUAAUUUUAAGCCCCUGCUGCUUUGUUGCAGUGAAAUGAUGGAGCCUUAAUUAUAGGCCCUGGCCCCCUGAGGUAGAAGCCUGGGUUGAGUAAGGCCCACUUAGCCCUCUCCCAGUCUCUACCCAUUACCACGGAAGGAAGCCAGAGACCAUGGACUCUGACCCUCUUCUCAGACAACAAUAGGAAUUGUCUUGCAGGGACUCUCUGCUGGUUGUUCCACGGCACUCAGCAAGUUGCUGGCCUCAAUACAUGUUAAAUAGCCAUGAUAAAGCUAAUGUCUCUAGGCCUUAGAAACUAGCCUAUCUACCUUUACCUCCAUUGACGAUAGGAUGCAGCUGAAGGGUGUUAAAAAGUCCUGGAGCACAUUGUAGAAGUGGCAGCUACAGCAUGGCACUUAAAGAGUUAGAGCUGGGGUAGAUACAGUGGAGAAGAGGAGCAAAAGACCCUCCCAGUAUUCUCAUUGUUGAGCCGGGUAAGCAAAAACCACUCCAUUAUGGGGAACCUCUGUGGUCCAGUAGGUGUUUUAAGACCUCCUCCACACUGCAGAGUUUCCAAGGCUGGGAGGAGGCCAAGCCACCUUUUCUAACUAUAAAACACCAAGUCUUACCUACUUCACUCCUUCCCCUUAGCUGUCACCCUCUGUGGGAUCCUGCAGUUUCUGUCUGCCAUUGGGCCUAAGAAUCAGGAAAUGGUUAUGUAGAGUCCUGAUAGUCUAACCCCUUAGCACAUGUGGAGCCCCUGUAGUCAGGCCUUAGAGGGCAGUAUAGCCAGUUCUAAAGAGAGUGAACAGCUCUAAGGGAUAAGAGAACACAGACGUAUCUUAGGAAGGUCUCAUUUUAACUGUUUUGCUAGUUAAGUAUGUUCUUGAUAGCCAAUAGCAGCCUGGGUGAGAAAGCACAUUGACUCAGGAGUCAAAAGACCUGGGCUUUUAGUCCCACCUCCUCCACUAGCAGUGUGACCUUGGAUAUGUCUUUUAAUUUCUCUGGGGCUCAGUUUCUUUGACUGUAAAAUGUGAAGGGAUUAGACUAAAUGAUUUUUCACGGCCUUCAGUUCUGUAAUGAAAAUUCUCUAACUCCGUAUCAUCAGCAAGAGUCUUUACAUCCAACGUGUUGCUAUAACUACCCCCUAAAGAGCUACCAACCCGUGUUCCAUUCCUAGGUAACAAACCUUGGCCUGGCCAAGGAUGAGUCACAGCAUUCACGGCUGCAUUUUUGGUACUCACGGGAUGCCUCUCUGAAAAGCUGUCCCAAGUGCCUGCUACAGAGGAGGAUAUACCAUGAUAGCAAAGGAAGGUUACUGCUGUAAAAGUGGAAACUGCAUGGAUCAAAGGGCAGGCCUACUGGGGUAAGGAACUCUCCCUGCAGCUCUGAGGAUACUUAAAUCUAGGAUCCUAGUCUUAGUCUCCCCCAACUCCUUUGAGGUUCCUUUCAAAAGUCCUUCUCCCACAGAUUGAAGCUGAAUAUAGUCUUCCUUGGGACAAAUGCAUUUGUCCAUAGGACUCUUUCCCGAGAUUGUUUUAGGCCCAUUUCUGUACCUCUCCCCUCAGACUGUUAGCCACAGACCCUUAGUCAUUGCAAAGUUACUGCAUAAUUCCCUGUCUGCUCAAAUAGCUGUCAAAAAAAAAAAAAGAAGGGUGUUAGGAAAUUGGCUCCUCAUCCUCUAUUUCUGAAACAGCAACUUCCUCCGCAAUUUCCUCUGAAUGCAUACCCAGGAAGCUGUUUUAAACAGCCUGAGUUGUGUCUUGUGGCACUAGGAAAGGGAGUAAUUUCUUGCUUUUUCACCUGGUCCUAGCCAAGUCCCACCCUUUGCUCUCCUGCAGUUUUCUUUCUUUUUAUUGGGGGUAUGGUGAUAAAGGAGAGGCAGGAGGAACGGAUCUUUGGUGCCUAGAACUGUGAGUGGUAGUUUAUAAGUGUGUGCCCAUACAUAUGUGCUGGCACACUGAUACCCAGAAAUGAUGUAUAUACCCAGGAGGAUUAAGAAUUGGCCCUUUCUUAGCCAACUGCUGCAAAGUGCUGCCUGCCUCUCUUUCCCUCCUUAGUGCCAAAGAGUUCACACCCACUCAGUCCCAAUUCCCUGCAUUAGUAUAAAUACUAGCACUGAAGAAAUGCAGGGUCCUGAUUCACGCAGCCUCUCUGGACAUUAUUACUUGGUAAGCAUCAGGAGACAGACACCUACCACCAAAACAUGUUUAGAUUAUUUAGCACCCAGAGAACAGAAGCAACACUGCCUGUGGGAAAUUUAAGCCAAACUACAUUAUUGCAGGCCUCUGAAAUCCAGGUCCCCCAGGUUCCUCGGGUAGAGCUGGUGCUGCCUGACCAGCAGCUUCUGCUGAGGUGGCAUUUAACUUUUGGCCAGGUCCCAGGAGCUGAGGCUGACCCAUUUCCCCUGCUUUUCCAGGGCAUAGGGAAUUUGAUUAUACCCCCAACAAAGCCAGGGACUAACACAGUUAGCUUGUAGAAGGUGCACUAGAAUCGGGGUGCUUUUAUUUAAGCUAAGGAAAGGUUGACAGCUUUAGCAUUUUCCCAUACUUGAAAAUAAUUUAACAUUUGUCUUUCCCCCAUCAUACCUGUACCCUCCCCUCCCCGCUUUUUUAUUAAAUAGAAAUGAUUGGCUCAUAAGAAUCUAUAGGUUCAGGGUCUUACUCAAUUUAACCCUUUGGGGACAUUGAAUUAAAAAUUCAACAAUAUUUAUUAAAAUA